GCACGCGCCACCACGCCUGGCUAAUGUUGUAUUUUAGUAGAGACGGGGUUUCUCCAUGUUGGUCAGGCUGGUCUCUAACUCCCGACCUCAGGUGAUCCACCCGCCUCGGCCUCUCAAACUGCUGGGAUUACAGGCACGCGCCACCACGCCUGGCCUAUUUUAUUUUAUUUUGAGACAGAGUGUCACUCUGUCCCCCAGUCUGGCGUGCAAUGGUUUGAUCUCGGCUCACUGCAACCUCCACCUCCCGGGUUCAACCUCCUGCCUCAGCCUUCCGAGCAGCUGGGACUACAGGAGCCUGCCACCACAUCUGGCGAAUUUUUGUAUUUUUAGUAGAGAAGGGGGUUCAGCAUGUUGUCCAGGUUGGUCUUGAACUCCUGACCUCAGGUGAUCCAGCCACUUUGGCCUCACAAAGUGCUGGGAUUAUAGGCAAGAGCGAUGGCGCCCGGCCCACUCAGCAGGAUUCCUAGAAUGGGCACGAGCUCUGCCCUCAUCACAGUCCAAAAGUGAGCACCUGCCUGGAGCUGCCCAGAAACAGCCUUGUGGGGUGGGGUUGGUGUCUGACCUCCCUCCCCGGGGGCCUUCGCAGGCUUCUCUGCUGGUGCUUCUGUGCCUGUGGGUCUGGAUUCCUCCAGGGCCUGAUCCUGGGUGCAGAUGCAGCUGGAAGCCCUGAACCUGCUGCACACACUAGUCUGGGCACGGAGUCUCUGCCGUGCCGGAGCUGUGCAGACACAGGAGCGGCUGUCAGGCAGUGCCAGCCCUGAGCAAGUGCCAGCUGGUGAGUGCUGUGCUCUGCAGGAGUAUGAGGCCGCCGUGGAGCAGCUCAAGAGCGAGCAGAUCCGGGCGCAGGCUGAGGAGAGGAGGAAGACCCUGAGCGAGGAGACCCGGCAGCACCAGGCCAGGGCCCAGUAUCAAGACAAGCUGGCCCGGCAGCGCUACGAGGACCAACUGAAGCAGCAGCAACUUCUCAAUGAGGAGAAUUUACGGAAGCAGGAGGAGUCCGUGCAGAAGCAGGAAGCCAUGCGGCGAGCCACCGUGGAGCGGGAGAUGGAGCUGCGGCACAAGAAUGAGAUGCUGCGAGUGGAGACCGAGGCCCGGGCGCGCGCCAAGGCCGAGCGGGAGAAUGCAGACAUCAUCCGCGAGCAGAUCCGCCUGAAGGCGUCCGAGCACCGUCAGACCGUCUUGGAGUCCAUCAGGACGGCUGGCACCUUGUUUGGGGAAGGAUUCCGUGCCUUUGUGACAGACCGGGACAAAGUGACAGCCACGGUGGCUGGGCUGACGCUGCUGGCUGUCGGGGUCUACUCAGCCAAGAAUGCGACAGCCGUCACUGGCCGCUUCAUCGAGGCUCGGCUGGGGAAGCCGUCCCUAGUGAGGGAGACGUCCCGCAUCACGGUGCUGGAGGCGCUGCGGCACCCCAUCCAGGUCAGCCGGCGGCUCCUCAGUCGACCCCAGGACGUGCUGGAGGGUGUUGUGCUUAGUCCCAGCCUGGAAGCACGGGUGCGCGACAUCGCCAUAGCAACCAGGAACACCAAGAAGAACCGGGGCCUGUACAGGCACAUCCUGCUGUAUGGGCCACCAGGCACCGGGAAGACGCUGUUUGCCAAGAAACUCGCCCUGCACUCAGGCAUGGACUACGCCAUCAUGACAGGCGGGGACGUGGCCCCCAUGGGGCGGGAAGGCGUGACCGCCAUGCACAAGCUCUUUGACUGGGCCAAUACCAGCCGGCGCGGCCUCCUGCUCUUCAUGGAUGAAGCAGACGCCUUCCUUCGGAAGCGAGCCACUGAGGAGAUAAGCAAGGACCUCAGAGCCACACUGAACGCCUUCCUGUACCACAUGGGCCAACACAGCAACAAAUUCAUGCUGGUCCUGGCCAGCAAUCUGCCUGAGCAGUUCGACUGUGCCAUCAACAGCCGCAUUGACGUGAUGGUCCACUUCGACCUGCCGCAGCAGGAGGAGCGGGAGCGCCUGGUGAGACUGCAUUUUGACAACUGUGUUCUUAAGCCGGCCACAGAAGGAAAACGGCGCCUGAAGCUGGCCCAGUUUGACUACGGGAGGAAGUGCUCGGAGGUCGCUCGGCUGACGGAGGGCAUGUCGGGCCGGGAGAUCGCUCAGCUGGCCGUGUCCUGGCAGGCCACGGCAUAUGCCUCCAAGGACGGGGUCCUCACUGAGGCCAUGAUGGACGCCUGUGUGCAAGAUGCUGUCCAGCAGUACCGACAGAAGAUGCGCUGGCUGAAGGCGGAGGGGCCUGGGCGCGGGGUCGAGCACCCCCUAUCCGGAGUCCAAGGCGAGACCCUCACCUCAUGGAGCCUGGCCACGGACCCCUCCUACCCCUGCCUUGCCGGCCCCUGCACAUUUAGGAUAUGCUCCUGGAUGGGGACUGGGCUGUGCCCAGGGCCUCUGUCCCCCAGGAUGUCUUGUGGUGGCGGUCGGCCGUUCUGCCCCCCAGGGCACCCCCUGUUGUAGGCACUGGCUAGGGAGGGGCAGGCCUCCUUCCUGCCCCUCGAGACACUCUUGGGAGAUGCAUUUUCCGUCUGGCUCACAGGGGGAGGGUGAGGCUUUGUACCCCAGCCCCUGCCCAGGCCACUGUGAGGGUGGGUGCUGGCUGAGCCCCUGGGGCAGAAGGAGUGGGGCAGGCGGGGUCUUUGUUCUCGGCUCCCACAGCAGAGCCAGGUGAGGGGGGGCCUGCCAGGACUAGACAGAAGUGGGGCGGCCUGAACCCUGCUUCCAGCCAUGGCCAGGGGCCACGGAACCCGGCAGGGGUGUCUGAGGCCGCCCUGUCAGCUGGCCGGUCCAAGCCUGUGGCUGGAGCUGGUGUGUGUUUAUCUAAUAAAGUCCCACAGGUGCCUCACCGCCGUGUCUCUCUAUUGACUGACACUGCUCGGGGUUUCAGGGGCGCCCUAGCGUCCUCCUGGGGUCAAAGGUGACAUAAGAGGCAGAGGCUGGAGCUUUCUGGAGAAUUUACUGAUCACAGAGCGGUGUGCUUCACAUCAGCCUCGCGCCACAUCCGAGUUGGGGUCUGAAUGCUGCCCGGGACUGCCGCCUGCGCCCCACCAGCCCCUCCCUCCUGAAGGAGGGGCACCCCGAGAAGAAUGAGGCUGCAGAGUGAUGUGGGGGCCAGCGGUGACUUCAUGACCACACUGCGCCCAGGUGUAAGAGGGCACGCUUCUGCCCAGGCAUCGUCCAUGGAAGACACGCAGUCGGCCACUGCAGCCUCGGUCCUGGGUGCCCUGGGGCUGGGUCACUGGGGGCCACAGGCCACACUGGGAGACCACAGUCCUGGCAUGCCAUGCAGCUCCCUGUCCCCAGAGGUCUGCUCAGAUGCAGAGAGCUCAGGAACCACACUCGCUGCCUGAAUUCUGGGAGCAGAGCGUGGUACCCACUGCCUGGCUGGGGCCUACUCUGGGACUGCAGCCCCUGUCCCCGCUGGCCCAGGCUUCCGGAGGCAGCUGCGUCCCUGUCUUGGCUCAAGGUCAGGCCGGAGGCCAGGCUGUCCACCUGCAUCUGGAACCUGCACAGUCACUCCUCCAGGUCCUCGCUGCUGGAGGACUCUCAGACAGGAAACCUUUGCUUUGGGGGCAGGGUGGGGUGCAGGGGUGGUUGGGGGAAUCACAGCAACGAGACAGCACAGUGCCAUGGCGCAGAGCCUCAUAUUGGUCGAUGAAACAAUGCUUUCUGAACUUUGUGUCCUUAGGAAGGGUGUAGGCUGUUGGUUGAAGUAGGAAACAGAAGAGGAGCCUGGGCACGCAACGGUCCCAUCGGAGAGCAGACCCCUCGGAGCUGCAGUGCUUGGAGGGGGGCGGUCUACCUCUGCUCGCUCUCUCCAUUUCUCUCUCUACCUCUGCUCGCUCUCUCCAUUUCUCUCUUUUUCCUUUUAGAGAUGGGUUCUUACUCUGAGCCCAGGCUGGAGUGCAGUGGUGUGAUUAUAGCUCACUGCAGCCUCGACCUCCCAGGCUCAAGUGAUCCUCCUGCCUCAGCCUGUCCAGUAGCCAUACCCUACUAGGCCCUAAUUAGCCCCAGAGGCGUGCACCACCACGCCCGCUAAUGCUAAAAAUUUGUUGUAGAGACCGAGUCUUGCUAUAAUGCCCAGGCUGGUCUCCAACUCUUGGCCUCAGGAGAUCCUCCCGCCUCUACAGGAUGAGCCACCAAGCCUGGCCUCAAUUCCUCUUUAAAGGAAUUGCCUAAAUCUUAAACCAGCAAUCAAUACUUUGUAUUUAAAAUUAAGCCAGGUUAGACUGGGCUAGGUGGCUCACGCCUGUAAUCCCAGCACUUUGGGAGGCCAAGGCGGGUGAAUCAUGAGGUCAGGAGUUUGAGACCAUCCUGGCUAACGUGGCAAAACCCCGUCUCUACUAAAAAUACAAAAAAAUUAGCCGGCAUGGUGGUAGGUGACUGUAAUCCCAGCUACUCGGGAGGCUGAGGCAGGAGACUCGCUUGGACCUGGGAGGGAGAGGUUGCAGUGAGCCGAGAUCACGCCACUGCACUCCGGCCUGGGCAACA